AUCCCAUUGUGUCACGAAUGGAGGAUAUAACUGGCUCAGACCAAAUCUUCUCACAUCCAAGAUCAAAUAGGGGUUUUUAAGCUUAUGGCAGUAGAAUAACAAGUACAUGUGGUACAAGGCUAGGAAACUGGGAAGGCAGGCAGCAGUAGAACCUUGAUCUAUCUUGUGGGAAGCUCUUAUGAUAGCUAAUUACACAUAUUGCUGGUCUAAAAAAUCAGAAUUACCCAGGCAACAUGGAAGAGGCAGAAUGGUUGGCUGGACUAGAAAACUCCUUCUUGGAGGCGGUCAUCUUCAUGUUGUACUAGAAAACUCCUUCUUGGAGGCGGUCAUCUUCAUGUUGUACAGAUGGCCUACGUAUGUGCAAUAUUUACAUCAUUGCGUUUCUUAGCACCACGGGCGAGUUUGGCAUUUUACAAGGUAGCUCACUCUGAAAGGUAAUUUUAUCAUAGUAUUUAGGAAAUAUUCCACGUCAGCCACUGAGUUUAAGAAACUGUGUGAAGAACUAAAAUUCUUCAUAGAGCCACAUUUGAGUAUGGAAUGAUUUGGUAUGCUGGAGGCCAUAGCACAUCUUUGAACAUCAAAUAAUUGGAUUUUUUGAGCAUCAAAUAAUUGAAUUUUUCUUUUCUUUUCUUUUCUUUUUUUUUUUUUUUUGAGACAGGGCCUCACUCUGCUGCCCAGUCUGAAGUGCAGUAGCAUGAUCACAGCUCACGGCAGUCUUGACCUCCUGGGCUCAAACGAUCCUCUUACCUUAGUCUCUCGAGUAGCUGGGACUACAGGCGUGCACCACCAUGCCUGGCUAAUUUUUUAAUUGUAGAGAUGAGGUCUCGCCAUGUUGCCCAGGCUGGUCUCAAACUCCUGGGCUCAAGCAAUCCUCCUGCCUUGGCCUCUCAAAGUACUGAGAUUAUAGGUGCGAGCCACCACAUCUGGCGUGAUUUUUCUUGAAGGCAGAUGUGGGCCUGAACUGGAGGAAGCCUGCUCUGAGCCUCACUCUAUCUUGAUCCCAGAAAUAAAUUUAUUGUAUAGCCUUAAGUUUUAGAGAGUUCAGGACACCUAGAGGAUGGUUGUGGUGUAAACUGCUUGCCUGGUCAAACCUUAAGGAUCUGCUUGGACUCUUCAGGACACAUACCCCGAGAGUGUCAGGCCUGAGCCCCAGCUGGUCCCAGAGGUUUAAUUCCUAGCACACCUAGUUUGUCUAACGUAGGGGUCUGCAAACUGUGUCUGCAAAGAGCCAGAUAGUGAAUAUCUGUUGCAAGUAAACGGUGUUGUCGUAGUACAAAAGCAGCACUAGAUGAUACGGAAGUGAAUGGGUGUGGGGCUCUGUGUCGAUAUAAUUUGAUUUGUGCUAUAGUUUGCUAACCCCUGAUCUGGAGAGAGGGCUCCCAAACAAGUGAGUCCACAUGCCUCCAACAGGACUGUGGGGGAUAGAACUCAGGAGGGAUUGGGAUAGGAAAAAAAAUCUAUCUGUAUUGUCACUAACCUCUAACUGAAACAGCGUUUGUUCUCUUACGAAUACAGGCAGCAAACCAGUGACUUAGCAAUACUUGUGACUUUGGUCAUUAAUAGAAAUCAAAGGUAAUUUCAUAUCCCAUUACAGUUAUUGCAGGUAUCUCAAAAUAUCAUUAAACUCAUCACUACUUUGGAAGUGUAUGUUAUACCUCCACUAGCAUUAACAGAACAUAUGUAUUCUACAUUUAUAUAAAAUUAAAUGAUUACAUAUAUUUAUUAUAUAUUAUGUAUUUCAAACUUGUUUUUUAUUUUGAUGUAUUUCAAUUUAGUUUUCUUUCUAAUGCUAUGUAUAUUUUUUCGUGCAUUUAAGAACAUUGUUCUGUAAAGGAGAUCUGGAGGGUUCAGCUGACUGCCCAGGGAGUCUAAGAAGCCCUGUCUAACUGGUGUCUUCAUAAUGGGGAGAACCUCCCCUUCCUCAAAUGAUCCUAUCCCUCUCCUCCCAGCCACUGAGGGGCAGUCAUCUCUAGCUCUACGGAGAUGCCCCCACCCCAUUUUCCCAUAUCAUAUUCCACCCAGCCUUCAAAGCCCUGCAUGAGUCCACCUAGUCCUUUGUUCCUCUGGCUCCACCACCCUGGCUGCCAGACACAGGCAUUCACCCCCGGCCCGUCUCAUGGGGUGUUCUAUUUGUUUAGUUUAUGUUUCAGCCCUAGUGAGAGUCAGUUCUGGAAUCCAAUGGAUCUGUGAUUCCUUGUUGGAAGGAACCACUUCUCUUGCGCUGAGUAACGCAUUGGUGUUGGAUGACGGUGUUCAUGAUGACGAACUUAUGCUGUCCUGACCAUGCCUGGAGACUGGCCCUGCAUUGGAGAAGAUCCAAGAGUCUGCGUGGUAAAAUGAUAAUGAACGUGAGCUUAGGGGCAGAAUGCUGAUGUGUUUAUUCUGCUAACUAUGUGCUUUGGGCAAGUGCCUAUACUUAUUCUCCCUGAGCUUCAAUUUCCUCAUUGGUAAAUUGGGGAUUAUACUUACCUUUCAGGAUGACAUCAAGAGUAAAUAAUAUACUGACUCUAAGAAAAGUGCCUGGAGUGGUGCCUGGUGCAUGGCAAAUGCUCAGUACCUGUGAGGUAGUAUUUGCCUGGGCUGGUUGAUGGUUGGGCGCUGGGGGUUAGCCUGGUAUAAAUCGAGAUUUUGAGGUGGUCCUGUGAACCCAAAGAUGCCUUGAGACCCUGCGUGGGAGACAGAUGGAAGGAGAUGUCUAAGCCUGGUGUCAAGGUGCUCUCACCUUGCAGAAUCACAGUGGGCUGUGGUGGACCAGGAGAAGACCCCUUAACAAAGUAUGGGAGUGAGUCUGUCUAAGUCAGCUAGCCCUUAAUGAGGUCCUCCUCGAGUGAAGCUCUGAUUCUGACACCCAUGUUAGGUUGUGGUCAUUUCUAGGACCCAGGGUCCAGCCCCAGAGAUUCCUAGAUAGUUCUAGGACCAUCUGGUGGAAUCAAACUAUGGAUAGACCCAUUAAUAUCCAACUGGGUCCUCUUUCGUUGAGUCUCCCGCCCUCUUGAGGGAGACUGAUCUUUAGUAACUUCUUUAUGAGACUGGGUCAGGUGGGCCUCCUGUUGUUGUCUGUGGUGCUGCAGGUCAUGUGCUUUGGUGGGCACCAGUAACUGUCAUUGGAAUUGCCAAGGUGGUGGGAAUAAAGAGAGAUGGGCUUCUCUGUGAUUGAAUUGAAGUUUGGUUGUGAGUGUGGGUCAUGAGCCCUGACCGGGUAGGAGACAGAAGCCUGUGGUUCUUCUCCUGGUUUCCUUAGGGAUUUUCAGCUGGCUCUUGGGCAGCUCCUUCAGGUGGUAGCUGUUGUGGCAGAAUAGAAGAGUGCUGGACUGAGGAGCAGAGACCUGGGUCUCAUGAGAUCAUGAGAUCAAACCACUUAAACUCUGUGUGCUUAAGUGACUUCGUUGGCAAUAGAGUAAUACCCUCCCUGAAGAAUAAAUGAGGCGAUGUUGAGAAAGCAUUUUAUGAGCAAGCCAUUUUCAUUAAUGCAAUGGGGGAAACAUGCUAUGUCUAGCUUAGAGGGCUGAAACGGUCAAAUGAAAUAAUCAACGUAAAUGCUAAAAAAAAAAAAUCCAGUCCACAUUUAUGGAAUUGCCUUUAUUGACAAAUUGAGCGAGGGUAAACAUUCGUGUAUUUAAGGCAUGGAGUGUUUCCCAGUUGCUUUUGAAGGUACCCAUUGUCACAAAGGAGUAAAGACCUUACUAAAUGGGAUCUUAUUUGUAUUUCUGUAGCAAAGGAUUUUUGUUAAAGAAGAUUCAAACUCAGAGAUGGUAGACUGAGUCUGCCAGGAAAACCACACACUUAUACUCCUGUUCCAUAGUCAACUAAUAUUCUGCUUCUGCUACAAACUUAAUGAUCAUAUAGGAAUUAUGAAUUUAGACCAACAAAUGCCAAAACUUGAACUAUACAAGUGUAUAGUUUUAGUGUAACUUUGUGUUGUCACUUUUUGCUUCUAUGUGACACUUAGCAAUUCUUUUUUUAAAAUAAAACAACAUUAGAGGUCAUUUAAUUGUAAUGACAAAUAAAAUCAGCAGGUAGACUUAGGAUUUCAAAGCAUCUCUUUCUUGGUUGGGAAAGCUCCCUGGAGGUCCAACUUGUAGUCCUAGGUUGAGUAGGGAUCAAUAGGAGAAUUUACUGAAGGGGCCCUAUGCUCAGUUUCACCAAGUUCACAGCCAGGUUCUUAUGAUCUGCAUCCUUCAGGUACAAGUGUGUGUUCUCUACUCCAGUAGCAGACUUGAACCCAGAGUCCCCAGUACAAGGAAGCACAUAUUUUUGGAUUUUGCCGUGUGACCUUGUCUGGCUGGCUGGACUUUAGGAACAACUGGUCCUCAUCCCUGGCAGGUUUAGGGGGAGAGUGAAACCAAGUCAGAUGACUCUGAAGCUCCUUCAAACACCACGACAGAAGGAAUGGAUUGAGCAAGAAUAAUUUUUAUAGACUUGGAAGUUUGAGUCCUUUUUUUUUAAAAAAAAAAACAAGGAAGUGGGGCAUUCCAGAUGGUAACACAAGAAACCAGGGAGAUGAGAGCAGAUGAAACCUUGAGGGAGAAAAUGAAAUUCUCUCUGAAUUAGGAGAAGCGGCUGCUUUCCCUCACAUCUUCCUGUGUCUGUAACUAGCUUAGUGUUUGGGAUGCUUAUUUUCUAUUUUCUCUGCAUUUUUUUAGCUGCCUCAGUGACCACUUGACCAUUUAUGCCGAGGCAGUAGUGGAUGUUUCCAAUUCAGUGCUCCUUACCUCUUAGAAAGAGAAGGAUUAUGCUUUCUUCAUGAUUGUGAGUCAGUCUAUGUUCAGAUUUACAUUCAACUAAUAUUUUUCAAAUAUUGGCCCAGAUAAUUUCAAGAUAUGCUAUCUGAUCCUCAAAACAAUCUUAUAAAUGAGGCUCAGAGAGGCAAAGGGACAUUGCAAGUCAUACAGGGGUUUGCAUAUAGCCUCCUCUCUGUAAGUCUAGAACCAUCUCUGCAGCUUCCUCCUGCGUUCACCAUGUUGUGUGACUUUUGUAAAUACUUGAACUCUAUGGAAACUCAGGAAUGAUGUGAAAUGUUAUUAGUUGGAAGCCUUGUCAGAGAAAAAUGGGCUAGAGAGUUCCGUUUGCAGGCUUGAGACUAUAGUUGAUGGGUCUGAUUCUGAAUUAAAACAUCCUUUAGAAAAUAGAUCCCGCUUUUUUUAGAGACUAUCCAAGAUUUAAAAGUUAAGCAGCUUUGGAAUAUAGCAGGCAGAUAGUUCUCCUGUAAUGCUUGCUUUGAAACCAUGAACAAUGUGUGCAUAAUCAGAAUCUUGGAUUUGCUUAAUACCAUUUUUUCUUGCUGAAACAUUAGGUGAAUGCAGAAAACUGCGCCCACCUGAACUACAUGACGUCAGAAUACACAAAACACGCACGUGGCACAACCUCAUAUGUCUACAGCUACCUCAGUUUACCCCGCGUGUUAAGAGCCACACCUGUCCAUACCUGGUGUUAUGACUGUCCCUCCAAUUUCGGGUAACCCUCCCUCCAGCCCUUCCCAGUAACUCACCAACCGCAGCCCUUCCGACACCCACCCCACAGCCAACUUCAGGCCUUUUUCUAGGCGAAGUGACACAUUUAUUGUUGUGUUUAUGUAUUUCUUAACUAUUUAAUGUGUGUAAAAUGGUGCUACUAUUUUUAUUAGGUUGCAAUCUUUUUGUAAAUGUCACUGAUUAAAUUUUUGAGUGUUGCUUUCCUAACCCCAUUUUUCCCAUAAGCCCUGUGUUUUUUAUUGUGCAUUUUGCAAAGAGUGAUGAUUUUUAGGACCACCUAUGAGGCAUUACCGAACAAGUGACUGUGUGAAGCUUUUGGACUAAACCUUCCAUCUAACUUCACUCUAUUAAAUGAGUUAUUUUCAGGAUAAGACAGUCUCAUCUAUUUACAAAUACUUUAUCAUAUAAUGAAGUUCUACUUAUGAUUUAUUCAGAAUCCACACAAGAAGGCGUAGAUUUGCUCAAGGAACAAAAUUAAUGACAUUUUAAAAUCUUACAACUGGAGAGGAUGAUUAAUGGGAAAAGAGCUAACAUUUCAUGAAAACUAGCUUUAUGCCAGGUCCUGUUGGAUGCCUUCCAAUAAUGACUGCAUUUCAUUCUCAUGUCAACCUGUUCGGGUGGUAGGGAAUUUUGGCAUGGAGAGAGUGAAAGUUGCUCAAUGUCCGUACAGCUCCUAAGUGACUGGGCUGCGAGUCACCACUGAGGAGCAGCCCAUCUGGAGGUAUGAUCACAGCAACAUGGGCUCCAGACUGUUCUUGGUCCUUGUUGUUCAUCGUCUUUCCCAUUCCAUACUUGCGUGUUUCUGUCUUCUGACACAAAUAGACUACUAGUGGGUUCCUGUGGGUUGCUGCUGACAAUCCAUCCAUUUACCCAGGCUACAUUUUUGUAUCCAUUUUUUUCAACCUUUUAAUUUUUUAUCACCCCACAACCUGGGAGACUUUUUAAGCAUUUUUUUUCCUAAUUGCCUCCCUAUGCAAUCUUUUUUUUUUUUUUUUUUUUUUUUUUGAGACAGAGUCUCGCUCUGUCAUCCAGGCUGGAGUGGCACCAUCUCGGCUCACUGCAACCUCUACCUCUUGGGUUCAAGUGAUUCUCCUGUCUCAGCCUCCUGAGUAGCUGGGAUUACAGGCGCCCACCACCACGCAUGGCUAAUUUUUGUAUUUUUAGUAGAGAUGGGGUUUCACCAUGUUGGUCAGGCUGGUCUUGAACUCCUGAGCUCAAGUGAUCUGCCCACCUCAGCCUCCCAAAGAGCUGGGAUUACAGGCAUGAGCCACCAUGCCCAGCCCCUAUGCAGUCUUAACACCCCAGAUACACUGCAUAUCUGUCUAUGUGCUGUGUGUAUAUUUGUGCUUUAUAUGCAUUAAAGAGUAAAGUUGUUUUUGCCCCUCAAGAAGUCAUUUUCAUCCUAUUGGGGUGAUCUUGCCUGUGUUGAAAAGGCAUGUUCUGUAUCUUCAGUUAUUUUUAAUAUGUAGAUCCGCUUUUAAAAUUAGUAUCAUGCUACCUUAGAAGCAUAUACCUGAGUUUGUGAAGACAAGCCCCCUUGUCUGGGCUGUGAUUCCUAGUAUCUUAUGAUGAGCCCGACAGGAUGACACAGCCAGGUGACUCACAUAGAGCUAAGCUCUGUGAGAAAGCGAGGCCUCAGAGGUAGCACAUGAUUUCCCUUCUUCCAGUUUCUCUAUAUAAAGAAAUAAAGAGCACACAUCAAACCAAACAUAAAUGGAAAGAAAUCAAUGGUUGAAUGACACAUGAUUCUGGCUUGUCAGCCCUAGUUGGCACCUUUCGCUCCAAAUCAUCAUCUUUCUAAGAUACUAAAUUAUAGAUUCCAACCAAGGUGAUUAGUGCUGCUCACACUUUAAUGUGCAUUGGCAUCACCCAUGAAUCUUGUUAAAUUGCAGAUUCUCAUUCAAGUAGGCCUGGGAUUCUGCAUUUCUGACAAACUCCCAGGUAAUACAGCCACUGCUUGGUCCCAGAACCAUACUUUGAGCAGCAGUAGCCUAAGAAUACACAGAGGCAAUUAAAACUAGCUCUCAAACUAUUUUAAGAAUUUCAGAAAGCCGAAAGCAGUGGUUCUCACUCAGAAGCGAUUUGUUCCCCAGGGGCCAUUUGGCAAUGUCUUGCAGACAUUUUUGGUCGUUAUAACUAGAGGAUGCUACUGACAUCUAGUGGGUGGAGGCCAGGGAUGCUGCUAAAUAGUCUACAAUUCACAGGACAGCCCCCAUCAGAAAGAAUUAUCUGGCCCAGAAUAUCCAUUGUGCUGAGGUUGGAAACCCUUGCCUAAAGGAAAUCACACACUUACUCCCAGUAAAGCAGCAUGGACAAAUACAGAUACCCUCUCUCCUUGGCAAGAGUGAUAUUCAAUUCAAUGUGAUAGCCCCAAAUAGUUUGUAGUGGUCAAGCUCUGCAGUUGACAUUAAUAGAUUACUCUAACUGAUAUGGGGAAGUAAGUUAAUUGUAAUAUAAAGAAAUGCAGUUAAGCAGAUUAAAAGGAAAACACUUUUGGAGUCAUGAGCUGUCAGAGGAGAUUUACAUGUAGCAAAGGAGACCCUGCUGGUUGAAGGAUGGGAAUGCCUGUCCCUUAUUGGGCAGGAAUUGGGUGGGCUGACCAGGCUGUGUACGCCUGGCUGGCACUGUUUAUUGGAGUGGUGUUCGAGCGAGCCCAUCUGGACAUUUUUGGAACAAACUUGGGACAUUCCUUUGGCCUUCUGAAUAUGACUUGCAGCUGGGUAGGGAAGUAGUGCAAUAUUAUCCACAGAUUGAAGAUUCUUUCAAACAACAGAAAUAAUCAAGAAUUCACUGUGGAGGAUUUUCCCCUCCAGAGAGUAACAGAUAGAUUGAUGCGUAGAUCUAGGUAUGCUUAUUAACAAACCAUUCCUGUUUCAUGGGAUGUACAUGUGGCAGCAUCUGGAUUAUUUAAUGUGUUAAUAUAGUCAGUUUGUAUAUGAAUAAUUUAAAACAGUAGCAAGAGAUAAAAGUAGCUCAUCUGAAGAAGGGUUGUUUGAGAGCUUUUUUUCUGUCAAGUAUAAUUUUACUCUCAGGUUAAAUGAAAUUUAUUAAGAUGCAAUUUGCUCCUGGGAGGUAUUUGUGAGUUUAACCACAGUCUGUCUUGGAAGAUAUUAUGACAGUAAGUAAAUGUCACCUGGAUAAUACUGAUCCAUUCACAGAAGGGAGAAAAAGUGUGUUGGGUCAAUUAAGGUGGUUUAAAAAUGUGUUGACUCUGAAGAAGAAAAGUAUCUAAAGUACACAACUCUAACAAAUCUCAAGGCCAGUGGGACUUUACAGACUGAGCCCAAUUGUGUUGAGUCUGUGUAUUGUAUAUACUUAACACAAGCAAACACAGACUUUUUCUACAAAUGAAAACAUGUCUGCUGAGCAGUUGACUCAGUCAUCUGGAAUAAAUGUUCUUUAUUUGUGUUUCCAUGGGUAAAAUCAAGUUAAUGAACUGAACCAUCACAAUUUCUCUUAUUUAAUUUUUAAAACUCUAGAUUACCCUGUCUUCUAUCUCUAUGUAAUUCCUGUGUUAGAGCAAACAUAGGAAAUUGUCAAUAUGGCAGAGUGCGGUGGCUCAUGCCUGUAAUCCCAGCACUUUGGGAGGCCGAGGCAGGUGGAUCACCUGAGGUCAGGAGUUCGAGACCAGCCUGGCUAGCAUGGUGAAACCCCGUCUCUACUAAAAAUACAAAAAUUAGCUGGGUGUGGUGGCACACACCUGUAGUCUCAGCUACUUGGGAGGCUGAGGCAGGAAAAUCACUUGAACCUGGGAGGCAGAGGAUGCAGUGAGCCGAGAUCACACCACUGUGCACUCCAGCCUGGGCGACAGAGCAAGACUCUGUCUCAAUUUGAAAAAAAAGAGAGAAAUUGUCAAUAUGGGGCCAUGUUUUACCUACAAAACUAGCAAUUUCAUGUUGUUCUGUCUAAUAUUACUUAGGAACAUUUUAAUUCUUGCAUUAAAAAGUAGCUUUUAUAAGCAUGAGGGUUAAUAUCUAGGCAUAAUGUGUUUUCUGAACAGCUGGCUCUGUUUUUCGUCUCUGUGCAGGAUAUGAUUUCACACCAGUAACCCUUCAACUUGGGGUGACACCUUUCAUAGGAGUCAUGGUAGUUCUUUCUGUUAUUUUUCUAGCCAUAUGGAGGUCUCAUUUCUCUUAAUUCUUAAAAUGAUGGACUACCUGUCUUCUAGCUGUAUAUUAUUUACUUUUUUGUUCAUAAGCACCAUACUUAAGAUUUUUUUCUUUUAUUUUUAAGGAGAAAAAAAGGCUGCAGUGAGCUAUGAUUAUGACACUACACUCACCCAGGAUGGAGUGCAGUGUCAUGAUCAUAGCUCACUGCAGCCUCGACCUCCUGGGCUCAAGAGAUCCUCCUGCCUCAGCCUCCCAAAUAGCUGGGACUACAAGUGUAUGCCACCACACACGGUUAAUUAAAAAAAAAAAAAAAAAGUUUUUCUAGCAACAGUGUCUCACUAUGUUGCCCAGGCUGGUUUUGAACUCCUGGGCUCAAGUGGUCCUCCCAUCUGGGCCUCGCAAAAUGUUGGCAUUACAGGAGUGAGCCACCAUGCCCAGUCCCAUAUUUAAGAUUUUUCUAAAGCCCUAAUUUUAAGAUUUUCAAAAAUGCUAAUUGUAUCCUACUGUUUCUGCCCCAAGAACCAGACACCUAGAUCUCAAGAUAUGGACAGGUAUUUAUUGGAAAGAAAUGAGGAUUUUGAGGUCAUAGAAGUGUCUAAAACAUCAAGAUUUAUUAAAAUGAUUUUUUACAGCUGAUGUUCUAACAUUCAUUAUUGUUUCCUAUGAUAGAGAUACAAAUUGAGUCACUUUUCAAACAUACUUUACUGUUGAAUACCUAUAAAAAUCUCAUGGAACUAGCAGUCCUUAGUAUACAGUCAGGAAAAUUCUGUUUUACACUAGUCACUUUCCAGAAAGGUUUAUUAAUAACUGGCUAUAUAAUUCUUUCCCCAGAAUAUGUUGUUCUUUGUGGAUUUUUUCACCCCCCACCCCCAGCUUUUGGUCUAUUCCAAAAUACACACGGGCUUGACCUAAGAAUUUUGCUAAAGGAAUUAUUCUCCUCUAGGGAAAUGAAGCAGCAUGUUUCAACACAAGCUUAGAAAUCUUAAAACAACUAAAAAUGAAAAAAAAAAGUACCAGGUCGUUAUUAUGUUCUGCAAAAAUUAGAUUUACGGGUUUUACUGUAGCCAUUGUCAAUGCCUUACUGAGGGAUAGGAUCAUAGCAGAAAGAUGCUAAGGAGCUUAUGGUCCCCCUGGGCUGUUGUGAUUAUGUGGAUAUAUUUAGAAGCUACAAAGAAAGCAGAGCAUCAGCUGAGAUGCCCCAGUAGACACUCUCAAAUUCAGAUCUCUCCCAUUAUGAGAAAAACCCUCAAAAGAAAAUAUUCACUUGGCAAGGAAUGAAGAGCUUUUUUACUCACCAAAAUGAUGUCGUAAUGUUUCAGGGAGAACAGUGACUGCGACUUACUUAUUAUUGUCAUUUAUAUCUCCUAGGGCUGAACAGUUGUCAGAGAGGAUAAGAGAUAGGGGGAGUGUAUGGGAGGCCUGCUUUGGUUCUCUGCUUAUAUAAACCUCCACAUUUUAGCAGAUUUAUGUUUCAUCCUUAAAAUGAGUUAAAAACAGCAGACCCUUUUGUUGCAGAUGCAAGAUAUAACAUGUAAAGUGGUUCCAUAGCAAAUUGCUAUUUAGAAAAGAACCCAACGUUAUUUUUAACCAACUGUUUGAUCUCCUGUAUUCUUUCUUAUGUGGUUUUAUGAAUUUUUGUUUCACUUGUAAAUAAUCGGUAGCAAAUGAGUGUGUGAGGCUAUGAUUUAAUUUGUAACAAGGUACAAUAAAAUACCUCAGCCUGUGACUCAACUAUUUUAAGAGGACAAAUAUGCUAAAUAGGAAUAUUCGUUUCUAACCCUAUAGUAAAUGAAAUGUACCUAAGAUCCAUGGCUGAAAAAACCUGCCUUAUACAAAUUCACAUAAGAGAGAUCAAAUGUGGUGAAGGUUGCUUGAUAAACUUCUAUUGUCUAGCUUGUCUGAUGAGCUAGAUUUCACAGUAUUAUGUCCAGAUUUACCACAAUAAUACUGCAUAGUUUUUUUCAAGUCUUCGAUCUAAGAGGUUCUAGUUUGAAGAGGAGGGGUUCUGUGUCAUUCAUACAGUGGCUGUGAUGCACAUCCGUUUGAUCUGUGGGCUCAUUUAAAGGCUUAGUGGACUGAAAUGUUUUGGGGUCACCUGGAGGGGAUCAGUGUGUCUGGGCUUUGCUUCCCUGUCUUCCUUACGUAUGUGGAAACGGUGAGUGUUGUUCCCUGAGAUGUCCUAGAGAGACAACCUUUUCCCAAGUGACAGUGAGUUUCCGUCUUGGAAUCAGCUUUGCUUAUCCCAGGGAGGAUCCAGGCCUGGCGCCAGCAAGUUCUCCCCAUGAGGUCUCUGAGGAUGUGGAGAGAAGGAAUGCCCUGCAGAGUUUCAGCCUGUUACUCUAAACCUCCAGGCAUGUUUAAGACCCCUUGGGAGAAGAGGAGGGAGACCUCCAUCCGUUUACAACAUCUCUGCACAGAAGGCAAAUUCUCUUCUCUUGCAUAGUACCCUAAUGGCAAAGGCAUACAUGCACCAGGCUCAAUUACUUUUAGUGAAGAAAAUAAACCAGAUCUGUGGAAGGCUUCCCUUCAGUGACUUGGGGAACUCUAGUUUAUGAGUGAAAGUAAAGAUACGAGCUAGUAGGUGACUUUUGGUGUAUGAGCCCUUAUUUGUGGGGUAUUAAAAACCAUGGGCUAUCCAGUAACUCAGUAACUCAGGACACACACAGCAUUUUGUGGUCCCUGAUGUCUUUCUUCGUUUUGGCUGCUGCUUUGGCCAUUCAGUCAAAUUUGACCAUUGGUUUUCAUUAAGAUUGGCCCUCAGAUACAGAGCAGGGAAAAGAAAUGAAAUUUAAGCUUGUACAUGAUAUAAAUUGUCAUCAACUCCAUUAAUGUGUUGGUCAGAGAGAAGGCGGAAGCCAAUAUUUGACAGGAAGCAUGUUUUUUUUUUUUUGUAGAUUCAGUGUGACCACCACACCGUCUCGUGCUUGUAGGUAAUUUAAUUUAACCUAGGAGGAAAAUCUAGUCAUUUGAGAAACUAAGAUAAUUAAUUAUAUGCUUUUAAGAUGGAGUUCUUAGAUGUGAGAUCUUGGAGAUCCCUGAGACCAUGUUUAAGAAAUGCUACAUUUGUACUGAAAAUCUUUGACUUGAUAUUAAGUUAUGAUAAACACAACUGCCAAUUCAGGUAUGUAAUUUAGGGAUGAAAUCUGAUCAUAAAAUGGCCGUCUAGAUCAGAGUUUGGCAAAGCAUGACCCAUGGACCAAAUCUGGCCCGCUGUUUUUGAACAGCUCACAAGCUAACAAUGGUUUUUAAAUGUUUAUUAUGUAUUUGUUUUUGAGUCAUGGUCUUGCUCAAGUCACCCAGGAUGGGGUACAAUGGUGCAAUCAUAGCUCACUGUAACCUUCAACUUCUGGGCUCAAGCAAUCCCAAGUAGCUGGGACUGCAGGUAUGCACCACCAUACCCGGUGAAGGUAUUUUAUUUUUGUAGAGACAUGGGAUCUUGCCCAGGCUGGUCUUGAAUUCCUGACCUCAGUACUCCUGCCUCGGCCUCCCAAAGUGCUGAGAUUACAGGUAAAGAUUUUGUUAUUUGCAAAGAGCUUUUCAGAGGAGGGACUAAAAUGAUAAUUCACCCUGUAUUUACUGGGUAAACAGUAUUAAGACCCCAGAUUUUGCCAGUAGCAGUGGCAUGUGCCUGUAGUCCCAGCUACUUUGGGAGGCCAAGACAGGAGAAUCACUUGAGCCCAGGAGUUUGAAUCCAGCCUGGGUGACAGUGAGACCCCAUCUAUUAAAACAAAACAAAAAACAGAUUUUGUCUGAAGAAGUGAGUAUUCUUGGACUUCUCAAAAUGUCAGUUUGGAGACAGUUUUGGUAGGCCACUUGGUAUAUAAGCAUGGACAGAAAUUGAUUGUGUGUGUUGUAUUAGGUUGGUGCAAAAGUAAUUGUGGCUUUUACCAUUAAAAGUAAUGGCAAAACCCGCAAAUAUUAUGAUCUAUGUUAGUCCAUGUGAGAGCAUAUUUAUGGAGAAUACUGACAUGAUUUGUCAAGUUAGUAGACAAAUAAUGACUGAACACUCAAAGGCAACAUGAUUAUCCUCCAGCUGUGCCUAGGAGAUUCUUGAUACCAUUUUACUAUGUCAAUAUUCAGCUACGUGGACAACCGCUAUUGUUUUGAACGCUCGCUUUUCCUUGAGAAAGGGAUUUCCAGAAAAAGAAAUUCUGUCAUAGCACCAAGAGCUAUGCUGGACAGGAGGUUCAAAUGUUCAUUUUUCUGGCCCUGAAAUGAAAUGCUUCUUAGGUACACAAUUUGCUGUCCAGGUCUAGAGCCGAGCCCAGCAAGAAACAUGCCCAGUGCAUGGUAGGCAGAAUUUUCUGCCUGUGGACUUUCACAAGGCUGCAUUGUGGGAACAGAAGCUGCUCAGAUUGUUCAUUGUUCUGUGACUCCUAUUUGGCAGCCAGUGGAGAAUUCAUUAUGCAGUGACUGGCAUACUUUUCUUCUGUUUUUUCCCUGCCCUGAGUACAGCAGUGCAUCCGUGCUCUCUGUAACCCCUUGCUUCACCCCUUACUGUUCUAAUCUUCCCCUCCUUGCCUUCCUCCAGCCUCACUGCUUUGCAAAACCUAGAGACAAGCAGACUUAAAUCAUAUGAACUGAUUAGGGGAUCAAUUUCCCCCAAUGCUGAGGAAACACACUUUGUUCUCACAUUUGGGUGGGUGAGCCUGCCACCAAAUAUUAAACACCCACGGACACAUAGCAGUGCGUCGGUUCCCCUUUUGGGGACUGCAAGCUCAGACAAAUGUCCACAAUGGCGAACAUGCCACAUUUCUCCCUCUGUGUUUCCGCCCCCAAAAGUGUGGCCUCCUGGGCUGAGAGGAAGAAAAUUGAGAAGCAGCUCUUUCAAAAUUACCAUUUGCAGGGUUUGUUGUUGUUGUUGUUGUUGUUUGGUUUUUUUUUGGUUUCUAUCUGACUUGCUUUGUAAAGCUGGAAGAAAAGAUUAGCAUGACUCCGAAAGCACUAUUUUUUAUGAAUUCCAGAGCAGCAGUUCUCAACCUUUAAAAUGUAUUUGAAUCACCUGGGGGUCUGGUUAAUAUGCAGAUUCUGAUUUGUUGGGUCUGGGGUGGGGCCAGAUUUCUAAUGACCUUCCGGGUAAUGCUGAGACUACUGGGCCAUGGACCACCACAUUUGAAUAGCAAGUAUUAGGUUGGUGCAAAAAUAAUUGUGGUUUUUGCCCUUUUUUUUGAAAGUAAUGGCAAAAACUGAAAUUACUUUUGCAUCAAUCUAAACACUAGUUCAGUGGCUCUCAACCUUGGCUGCACGUUGGGAUCACCUGGGGAGCUUUAAAAACUACUGAUGCCAGAGCCCCACCCUCAGAGAUUCUGGUUUAACUGGUCUGGAGUGUGAUCUGAGCCUAGGGAGUUUUUUAAACGCCUCAGAUGGUCUCAAUAUGCACCAUUGUGGUUAUAUUGCAGCUUUACAGGUGUAAGAAUCGGAUUUGUUCUCUUAAAAGGGAAGAUAAGUCUUCUUUUUGGUCCUAGGUCAAUCUGAGCUGAGUUCUUCAGCCCUUGAAGAAAGAGCAUCCUUCUAACUCACCAGUUCUCAACCAGGGGACAUCUGGCAGAUGCGUUUGGUUGUCACAACUGGAGUUGGGGGUGCUACUGGAAUUAAGUGGAUAGAGUCCAGGGGUGCUACUAAACAUCCUACAGUGCAACAGCUCCCCACAGCAAAGAAUGAAAGGGCCCCAAGUAUCGAUGGUGCUGAGACAGAAACCCUGGUAUAGCUUACCUCACUCCUGCCCUCAAAAGGCUGGGAAGUUCAACACUUCCUUCUUCAAUGACUAUUGAGAGUAACUAACUAAUAGUGUUACAACAAAGGGGUCCCAAUCCAGAUCCCAAGAGAGGGUUCUUGGAUCUCAUGCAAGAAAGAAUUCAGGGCGAGUCCAUAGAGUAAAGUGAAAGCAAGUUUAUUAAGAAAGUGAAGGAAUAAAAGAAUGGCUACUCCAUAGAGCCAUUUUAUGGUUGUUUCUUGAUUACAUGCUAAACAAGGAGUGGAUUAUUCAUGCCUCCCCUUUCUAGACCAUAUAGGGUAACUUUCUGACGUUGCCAUGGUAUUUGUAAACUGUCAUGGCGCUGGUGGGAGUGUAGCAGUGAGGACAACCAGAGGUCACUCUCAUCACCGUCUUGGUUUUGGUGAGUUUUAGCCAGCUUCUUUACUGCAACCUGUUUUAUCAGCAAGGUCUUUAUGACCUGUAUCUUGUGCCGACCUCGUAUCUCAUCCCGUGACAUAGAAUGCCUUAACCAUCUGAGAAUGCAGCCCAGUAGGUCUCAGCCUCAUUUUACCCAGCUCCUAUUUAAGAUGGAGUUGCUCUGGUUCACAUGCCUCUGACAAUAGCACGUAGCUAAUAGCAUUUCUUUCAUGUCUAAUUCUGUUUUACAACACACUACUGUCGCAAGUAUUCUGAACUGGAAAGUCAGUCUUCCUCCCCUGUAAAAUUAGGCUAUUGAAAUACAAGCUUCCAAAGUCCUUUUCAGUUAAAAAAAAAAUUAUGUGAUUGGCAGGGGGAAUGGGGAGUAGUUAUUUCAUGGUUACAGAUUUUCUGCUUCUGGUGAUAAAAAAAAAAAAGUUCUGGAAAUGGGUGGUGAGAGUUACAUAACUUUGUGAAUGUCGUUAAUGCCACUGAACUGUAAAGUUCAUGUUAUGUAUAGUUUACCACAAUUUUUUUUAAAAAAAACCAUGAUUCUGAGAUCAUUGGUUGAACCAUAAACCAUAUGCUUGCCUGCAUCUAAUGUGAAACCAUCCCUGCUCCAUGUUCUUAGCAUCCUAGGUUCGUUUCCUUCUUGGCACUCACCGUGGCUUGAAAUCACAUGGAUUUAUGUGAUUAUUUGAGUAUGCCUUUCCCCACUAAACUGUCAGCUUCAUGAAGGUAAGAACCAAGUCUGUUUUAUUCUUCAUGGUACUCCCAAUGCCCAGCACAGUUUUCCUGGGAUUUAGUAGGCAUUCCACAGAUAUUUGUUGGGUAGGUGGUUUUACUACUAGUACAUAUGUUAACCUCCCUAGGAACAGGAAUUAGCCAUUAUCCACACAUUUGUAUUUAGUAUCAUCUGUCUCCUAGCCCUUUGCUACUGGAGGAAUUGUGGAAUGGAGAGGUUAUGGCUAAGUACUAUUUUAUGAUGUUAUUCUCUGGGAAUUGGCUUAGAUUAGAAUCACCUGGAGUAGUUUUAUAAUUAUUAAUGGCCACAUCACAAGGAUUCAGGUUCUUCAGGUUCUGUUGAUCUGCGGUGGGGUUGGGCAUCAGUAGUUUAUAAAGGUCUCCAGUUAAUUCCAACGUGCAUCAAGACGGAAAACCACCGUGUAACUCCUUGCUUCUCAAAAUGUCCCAGGACAAAGGCCCCAGUGAACAGCAGAGCUGAAAUGGAAAUUGGCAGGUACCACUGGAUGUACCCAGGCUCAAAGAACCACCAGUACCAUCCCGUGCCAACCCUGGGGGACAGGGCUAGCCCCUUGAGCAGUCCAGGCUGCUUUGAAUGCUGCAUCAAGUGUCUGGGAGGAGUCCCCUACGCCUCCCUGGUGGCCACCAUCCUCUGCUUCUCCGGGGUGGCCUUAUUCUGCGGCUGUGGGCAUGUGGCUCUCGCAGGCACCGUGGCGAUUCUUGAGCAACACUUCUCCACCAACGCCAGUGACCAUGCCUUGCUGAGCGAGGUGAUACAACUGAUGCAGUAUGUCAUCUAUGGAAUUGCGUCCUUUUUCUUCUUGUAUGGGAUCAUUCUGUUGGCAGAAGGCUUUUACACCACAAGUGCAGUGAAAGAACUGCACGGUGAGUUUAAAACAACCGCUUGUGGCCGAUGCAUCAGUGGAAUGUUCGUUUUCCUCACCUAUGUGCUUGGAGUGGCCUGGCUGGGUGUGUUUGGUUUCUCAGCGGUGCCCGUGUUUAUGUUCUACAACAUAUGGUCAACUUGUGAAGUCAUCAAGUCACCGCAGACCAACGGGACCACGGGUGUGGAGCAGAUCUGUGUGGAUAUCCGACAAUACGGUAUCAUUCCUUGGAAUGCUUUCCCCGGAAAAAUAUGUGGCUCUGCCCUGGAGAACAUCUGCAACACAAACGAGUUCUACAUGUCCUAUCACCUGUUCAUUGUGGCCUGUGCAGGAGCUGGUGCCACCGUCAUUGCCCUGAUCCACUUCCUCAUGAUACUGUCUUCUAACUGGGCUUACUUAAAGGAUGCGAGCAAAAUGCAGGCUUACCAGGAUAUCAAAGCAAAGGAAGAACAGGAACUGCAAGAUAUCCAGUCUCGGUCAAAAGAACAACUCAAUUCUUACACAUAAAUGUUUGCCAGAGUGUUUCGGCCGACGUAUUUACAGCUCUGACAAAUCAUCAGACAGCUGCUCUGCAGUACAGAUGUGUAUCCCACCAAACUAAUGUAGAUGUACAAACACUUCACUGUCUGUCUCAAGCUGCUGGGAUGUAUCUCUAGGAAAACCUUCCAGUGGGUAAAUCUUUUUCUUUAGAACAAAUAUUGGAGGUUUCAUGUUAGCCAUUUUAAAAGGCAACACUUUGACAAAAUGAUCGUUCAUACUUUGGGAAUUUGUGGCAUGUUCACAUUUAUUGCUAGGGCAAUUCUACCAAGACACUCAAUGGAAUAUGUCACACUCCUUAAUAGGGACCUGUGACUCCUUAAUAAGGACCUGUGACAUGCCCAGCAUCAAGGGAUAAGACCGUAAAUUCACAUAUAUGCCAUCUGUCCUCAAGUGUUAUCUACAUAGGAAAUAAAAUGGAAUUGAUGUAAAGUUCCAUUUCUGACAGCUGACAUUUAUUAAACUUUGGAUCAAAGAUAAUGUGAUUCUUAUGAUUGAUUUCUCAAACUAGCUUUUCCCUCCCAAGUCCAGGACCCAUUAAUUUCCUGAGCCAAUCAGAAAUAUAUUUUUCAAUAAUGCUAAAAUUAGCUACAAUUCUGCUGACCCUACUAUUAAAGAAUCUGGAUGCUGGACUCACUGACAAGCUUUCCAGAAGCAAUUUUAUAACAGAUUUCAUUUUAACAAAAUACUGAUCCAAUUUUCAUUAUUCUUGAGAAAUGUCAGCUUUGCCUUAAUGAGUAUUUGCUUUAAAUUUCUAAGAAUUUAUAUCAUAACUAGAGACCCAAAUAUCUUUCACAGAAUUUUGUUCCAUAAAUGUUUUUCUUAAUUAUUAAGAAGUGUUACCUUAUUAAAAUGACCACCAUUCUAAACCAUUUUUCAGUGGUCUGGAUACGAAGUUUACAGUUUCAUACCAACUAUCUAAAACCUAAUUGCAAAUUGACCACAGACCUCUAACCUCCUACUUUUAUAGACUUGAAUACUUAAGUAAUUUAAAUUAGGGUUGGUAUUUCAUUUUUUUCUUAUCUAAAUCUUAGUUUCCUGGAAUAAUAAAGUUUGAUGUUCAGCAAGAGAACUGCUUGAGUUUAAGCCAUUUUCAAAAGAAACUUGCCUUUUACAUUAUUGUGUUCCAGAACAUUAAGUGACUGUAGGUACUGGGUAUUAGUGAUGGUAAACUUUGUGUUGCUCUUUAUGAAAUGAUCCAUAUAACUGUUGGGUGCAUCAGUGCUUUUCAAAGGGGCUGCUUACUAUAGGGUUAACUAUGUAUAUUCAUUGUUAAGAGUUAACUUGUGGUUUGGCUGUUUCCUGGAUUUUAUAACAUACAUGUGCAGAAAUGUAUUCAAAUGAAAGGAAGCAUACCUUUAUCAAGAUGCUAUUAAAAUUGAACAUCAAGUAUAAUAUUUCAUUUGGAUUCUCUUUUUUGGUUAAUGCCUAAAAAUGCCUAUUUGGGAUUUUUUUUUUUUUUUAAAUUAAGAGAAGCUCUCUUCUGUGUAGAACAGUUGUUCCAAAAUAGCUUAGUGUUUUGUUUUCCUGUUGCAUGACAGAUUUAACUAUUCUUUCCAGCAGUGGAGGUGCUGUCAGAGUCCAGUGUUCUAGAAGAGGCAGUGUCUAAAGCCUAAUUUUACUUUUCUAAUUCUGGUAGCUAUUACCAGGAAUUUUUGAAAGUUUUGUUUAAGUAGUCUAAUAUUUUUUAUGUAAAGAGCAUUAAAUUUUGCUAUGUAUAAAUUUUUGUAACCUAACAGUGAAUCAAUAUUUUCUAUCAGUGCCAAGGGCUUCCUGUAGUUCUAUUCAAGUGUUACAAUAAAUAUUUGUAGAUAAUAGUCAAUACUUGUGUAUGCUUAUUUUAAAGAUCUAUUUAGGUGGAAAUAGUUGUGGAUGUACUAAGAGUAAUGAAAUAAAAUUAUAGCUUCAUUCA